GCUCCGCGGCCCAGCCUGGCGCUCGAGGAUUGCCAGGGCCGCCCUGUGCCCUCUGGCUCGGCGGUGGUGGGCGAGGGCUCAGGGAUCGGAGAAGUAGCGUCUUCCCGGGGGUGCCGAAUUGGCGGGGCUGGGGGACGCUUUUUUUCACCGCCGCCCGCCGAGACUACGGCUGCCCGAGACUGCCGCCCUCCGACAGCGCCCAAGCCUCCGGCCGCUGCGGCCAGUGGGCCAGGGUUCGGCGAGCCUUCCCUGCCGGCGCCGGCCGGCUGCUGAGGCGCUGGGAGGAGCUGCGGAGGGCGGGGACUGGUGUCGGAGAAGGGGCGGGGUGGGAACGCCGGAGAGAACCCGGUGGCUGCACAGACAAAAAAGCCCCGAAUGGCUGGAGGGCGUUCAGCUGUUAACAGCCUUUUGGGGCAGAGCACGGAUUUGACAGCUCCACAACGUGAGGAUAUCCACUGACCCCGCGAGACGGAGGAGAACGCUUCCCCGAAAUUCUCUGCCCACCAAAGCCAGCGCUGCAAGGUUGCAACUUUCAAACUUUGUUUUUCCAGAAAGAAGACUGCCCUUUCGUGUACAAGGAGAGGGUGAGAGGGUGACCUAGCUUGUAGAUCGGCUGAAGGCACCAGUGGUUCCAAAUGUCACCCAGAUGUGUGUUUUCAUGACGAUUUGAUUUCUCUGAUUUUAUUUUUACAUUUUUCAUUUUAAAAAUACAAAGCAAUUUUUUUGGGGCAUGCUGAAAGGUAACUGAAGACCGCAAAGGAAAAACUAUUGUCAUGGCUGAAGGAGAGAAUGAAGUGAGAUGGGAUGGACUCUGCAGCAGAGAUUCAACUACUAGGGAGACAGCAUUGGAAAACAUUAGGCAAACCAUUUUGAGGAAAACCGAGUAUCUUCGUUCGGUGAAAGAAACACCUCAUCGUCCAUCAGACGGGCUUUCAAAUACCGAGUCUUCGGAUGGGUUGAAUAAGCUACUUGCUCAUCUGCUUAUGCUUUCUAAGAGGUGUCCCUUCAAAGAUGUGAGAGAGAAAAGUGAGUUUAUUCUGAAGAGCAUCCAGGAACUUGGCAUUAGAAUUCCUCGACCACUAGGACAGGGACCAAGCAGAUUCAUCCCAGAAAAGGAGAUCCUCCAAGUGGGGAGUGAAGACGCACAGAUGCAUGCUUUAUUUGCAGAUUCUUUUGCUGCUUUGGGCCGUUUGGAUAACAUUACGUUAGUGAUGGUUUUCCACCCACAAUAUUUAGAAAGUUUCUUAAAAACUCAGCACUAUCUACUGCAAAUGGAUGGGCCGUUACCCCUACAUUAUCGUCACUACAUUGGAAUAAUGGCUGCGGCAAGACAUCAGUGCUCCUACUUAGUGAACCUGCAUGUAAAUGAUUUCCUUCAUGUUGGUGGGGACCCCAAGUGGCUCAAUGGUUUAGAGAAUGCUCCUCAAAAACUACAGAAUUUAGGAGAACUUAACAAAGUGUUAGCCCAUAGACCUUGGCUUAUUACCAAAGAACACAUUGAGGGACUUUUAAAAGCUGAAGAGCACAGCUGGUCCCUUGCGGAAUUGGUACAUGCAGUAGUUUUACUCACACACUAUCAUUCUCUUGCCUCAUUCACAUUCGGCUGUGGAAUCAGUCCAGAAAUUCAUUGUGAUGGUGGCCACACAUUCAGACCUCCUUCUGUUAGCAACUACUGCAUCUGUGACAUUACAAAUGGCAAUCACAGUGUGGAUGAGAUGCCGGUCAACUCAGCAGAAAAUGUUUCUGUAAGUGAUUCUUUCUUUGAGGUUGAAGCCCUCAUGGAAAAGAUGAGGCAGUUACAGGAAUGUCGAGAUGAAGAAGAGGCAAGUCAGGAAGAGAUGGCUUCACGUUUUGAAAUAGAAAAAAGAGAGAGUAUGUUUGUCUUCUCUUCAGAUGAUGAAGAAGUUACACCAGCAAGAGCUGUAUCUCGUCAUUUUGAGGAUACUAGUUAUGGCUAUAAAGAUUUCUCUAGACAUGGGAUGCAUGUUCCAACAUUUCGUGUCCAGGACUAUUGCUGGGAAGAUCAUGGUUAUUCUUUGGUAAAUCGCCUUUAUCCAGAUGUGGGACAGUUGAUUGAUGAAAAAUUUCACAUUGCUUACAAUCUUACUUAUAAUACAAUGGCAAUGCACAAAGAUGUUGAUACCUCAAUGCUUAGACGGGCAAUUUGGAACUAUAUUCACUGCAUGUUUGGAAUAAGAUAUGAUGAUUAUGACUAUGGUGAAAUUAACCAGCUAUUGGAUCGUAGCUUUAAAGUUUAUAUCAAAACUGUUGUUUGCACUCCUGAAAAGGUUACCAAAAGAAUGUAUGAUAGCUUCUGGAGGCAGUUCAAGCACUCUGAGAAGGUUCAUGUUAAUCUGCUUCUUAUAGAAGCUAGGAUGCAAGCAGAACUCCUUUAUGCUCUGAGAGCCAUUACCCGCUAUAUGACCUGAUGCCUUUCCUUCAUUAAAGAUGAUUCUGGAAUGAUCAGCAGAUAUAGUCUACAAGGGGGAAGGUACUAAGCCCCAGGACCAAUGGUAGACAAAAUAAUUCAGAAAUCCAUUGUGCCAUGAUUCCUUUAGUUUCUGCUAUUUUUCUGUGGAAAACCACUGCUGGCACAAGCAGUGACUGUUUGGCAGCUUCAAGUUUAGAGCUGUGAAGACAGGCUGCCAUUCACAGUAUUUUGCUUUUUGACAGUACAAGAUGCUGUGUAACUGUUUUAAUACAGCAAAUAGUAACUCUCCAAAUCCUGUUGCUUUUAUGUUAAAUAAGAUAACAAGAAUUGGAGCAUGCAAAGAAUGGGACUUGGAUAAUGACUUAAGCUUUAUAUGUAAAGAAUUUUAGAAGAUCUUGGUGCUGCUAUUCCUGCUGGAGGAAUGAAUAGAUGGCUGUUUCAGUUAAGCUAUUAGUAAUAAAAGUGAACAUUGCUACUAUCUGAGCCUACAUACAUAACUUGUGUGAUUUCAAAUUAAACUUGCAUUAUGUGUUAAUUUUCUUGCAUCUAAAAAAGCAUAGAAUUCCUACUCACACAGCUCAGCAACAACCAUUUUGAUGGUAACAGUUAAUUUCUUUCAUUAGUUUUUUAAAUUCAGGGUUCUGGAUAUUAAAUUAAAAUGGCAUUCUUAAAGAUUUUCUUCAAAAAGCAAUCCUAAAUGAAAGUGUGUAAAUUAUAAGAAGCUGGCGAUCUUUUGAUAUGCUGUUUCACAGGAUCCUGACACUGGAGGGCAGCUGUCUUGUGCAUUACUUGUGUUUCCAGCACCAAAGUUGUGGGACAUGUUGCUGUAGACUGCUGCGCAGUCCUGGGUGCAUUCAGUCUCUCUGCCUCUGCCUGCCUCCUGGUCCCCACUUUAAAGGCUGUGCAGCUCCUUAAAUAAUAAAGCUGGAAAAUAUUUUUAGUCGGGUUAUCAAAUUUGAUUUACAAAAACGCUAACUUUGUUUGAAAUGCAAACAGGUUUGAAAAUAUGUAUUAAGUACUUUGUAUUCUGGAAGCGUGAAUUGCUUUUGAAGUCUGUCAGUAUUACUGGUAUUUUUAAAUAAAGAAGAAUUUUUCUCCAAUUUUAUUUGCUGUCUCAAUCUCUUAAAAAAUCAUGACUUCACUAUUAGUAAUAAUUUUGAGUUUCUAUCUACUUUCAUAAGCCAAGUACAUUCACACUUAAAUGGCAAAACAACACUUGAAGCCAUUUUGAAACAUACAAAGAGGAGUGGACUUUCUUUAGAAUCUUAUCUGAGACCAUUUUUAUCUUGGAAAUGACUGGUAUGGCCCUAUGCCUGCUCUCUUUUCAACUGUUUUAGAGUUCCAAUAGAAUUUUAAGAAUUACUAAAAAGAAGGAUUCAUUAGGGAGAGACUACAGAACAAAAAAUGACACUCAUCAGACAAGUAGAAAUAGCUCUAAGUUUAACUGAAGCUGUUGUGAUGAUAACUCUGUUAGUUACUCCUCAAAACAUUUAUUGAGCUCAAUCUAGUGCCUGCCUACAAAUGUAUGGGGUAGUGUGGAAGUAGGGGUUGGGAAGGAUCAAUUUUGAACAGAGGUGGUACCUGUCCUCAAGGAUAUUUACUCUCAUGAGAAGACAAGACUAUAACCUUAGCUAGGAAUAGAGUAUUAUUAUCUUCAAUAUGUUUUAUAUUUAAAGAAACUUACUUAUAAGUGCAUUACUCAUUGAAUAUGCAUCAUGCCUUUGUCCUCUUCUGCCUGCUGCUGAGUUCUCUCACCAGAGCAAUACAAUUGAACCCAAGAAGAUAGUUAAAAUUUUACUUAUCCCAUUUCUGCUCUUUGUUCCUCCUCUUGAAAAUACAAAAUUUCUAGUAGAGAUUCUAAUCAGCAGUAGAGUGAUCACAAAACAAGAUCAACUAGAAUGCAUUUAGUCCACUGGAACUUAUAAUCACUUAGAAAUUGAAAUCAAAAUUUUAAUGAGUUAAAAAAUAUGUUUAUACCUAAAGUAAUAAAAGUGCAUGUGAUACAAAGUUAAUGUUUCAAUGCCUUCCAUUUAGCAGGUGCUUCCUGUUGGAGUGUUUUCUCAAAACUAAACACACAGGAUUUCUAAUGUUACUAUAUAAUCUUUGAAACCAGUAGUUUCCAAAAUAAUUAGGGAAGGUACAUUACACUGGGGAUAUCAAAACCUUCCCCAACCAGAGGAAAAUUUUCUUCUAAAAUAAUCAUGAGAAGAUUUCUGGUUGAGGGUCCCAGGAUUCAAGAGUUAAAAUCUUGAGUUGUUUUGGCCGUAUUUGGGAAAAUUUUUUAUUAGGCCAAACUUUAUCAUCUCUAAGAAUGAGAUUGAUUUUGAUACAGACCACCAGGAGAUAAGUAGAUAAGUAAAACUUGUUGGAUAAGCACUUUUUAUCAAUAUACUCUGAAAUUUUAUUAGCAUAUUCAUAUAUGUGAAUAUCAUACAUGAAUCAGAAAUGUUACUAGCAUAUUUGUAUAUGUGAAUAUCAUAUAUGAAUCAUCAUACUAGUUUUUUGCUAACACUGGUAGAUGGGAGUAAUGUCAGCAAGAUGAUGGACUUGGGAACUCCACGUCCUCAUUCUCCCAGAGACGCUGAGUUAACAAUAUAUGGGCCAGAAUAUCUUUGUGAGAACUCUAGAAACCAAUUGGGAAACUGCAGCAUUUAGGCAAAUGCAAAGCCAGGAAAAGGCCGCACCAAAAGGCUAGGAAAGUUUGUGGAUUUUGCUCACCCUAGCUCUUCCCCAGCAGAGGAUGGUGUGAUCAAGAGGAAGCAUAAAUUCAGCAAAGUUGUAGGAUACAAAGUCAGCACACAAAAAUCAGUUGUAUUUCUAUACACUAACAAUGAAUGAUCCAAAAAAAUUUAACAAUUCCAUUUACAAUAGGAUCAAAAAGAAUAAAAUACUUAGGAAUAAACCUAACCAAGGGGAUAUGUGAUGGCUGAAUGUUUGUGUCUUCCCCUACAUUUGUAUGUUGAUGUAUGUUGUAUGCUGAAAUGUAAUCCUCAAUGUGGUGAUAUUAAAAAAGUAGGCCUUUGGGAGGUGAUAAGAUCAAGAGGGCUCUGCUCUCAUGAAUGGGAUUAGUGCCCUUUAAUAGAGGUCUGGGGAGCUCCCCUUCUACCAUGAAAGGACACAGCUAGAGUGUGCCAUCUGUGAGGAAGAAAACACUCACUAGGCACUAAAUCCUUGAUAUCGGACUUCCCAGCCUCCAAAACUGUGAGCAAUAAAUUUCUGUUAUCUAUAAAUUA